ACUUCAUGUUUUGGAUGCUGCAUGCUGGGUGAGCGGAGAUUCCAGGCACUGGCCAGGGCAGCUGCCCUGACUCCAAGGGCUGCCAUGAACAACUUCCAGGCCAUCCUGACUCAGGUGAGAAUGCUGCUCUCCAGCCAUCAGCCCAGCCUGGUGCAGGCCCUCUUGGACAACCUGCUGAAGGAGGACCUCCUCUCCAGGGAAUACCACUGCACUCUGCUCCAUGAGCCUGAUAGUGAGGCUCUGGCCAGGAAGAUCUCUUUGACCCUACUAGAGAAAGGAGACCUGGAUUUGGCCCUCCUGGGGUGGGCCCGGAGUGGGCUGCAGCCCCCAGCAGCCGAGAGGGGCCCCGGCCACAGUGACCAUGGUGGCAGCUCACAGUGUGCCACCAUGGAGUUGGGGCCCCUAGAAGGUGGCUACCUGGAGCUUCUUAACAGCGAUGCUGACCCCCUGUGCCUCUACCACUUCUAUGACCAGAUGGACCUGGCUGGAGAAGAAGAGAUUGAGCUCUACUCAGAACCCGACACAGACACCAUCAACUGCGACCAGUUCAGCAGGCUGUUGUGUGACAUGGAAGGUGAUGAAGAGACCAGGGAGGCUUAUGCCAAUAUCGCGGAACUGGACCAGUAUGUCUUCCAGGACUCCCAGCUGGAGGGCCUGAGCAAGGACAUUUUCAUAGAGCACAUAGGACCAGAUGAAGUGAUCGGUGAGAGUAUGGAGAUGCCAGCAGAAGUUGGGCAGAAAAGUCAGAAAAGACCCUUCCCAGAGGAGCUUCCGGCAGACCUGAAGCACUGGAAGCCAGCUGAGCCCCCCACUGUGGUGACUGGCAGUCUCCUAGUGGGACCAGUGAGCGACUGCUCCACCCUGCCCUGCCUGCCACUGCCUGCGCUGUUCAACCAGGAGCCAGCCUCCGGCCAGAUGCGCCUGGAGAAAACCGACCAGAUUCCCAUGCCUUUCUCCAGUUCCUCGUUGAGCUGCCUGAAUCUCCCUGAGGGACCCAUCCAGUUUGUCCCCACCAUCUCCACUCUGCCCCAUGGGCUCUGGCAAAUCUCUGAGGCUGGAACAGGGGUCUCCAGUAUAUUCAUCUACCAUGGUGAGGUGCCCCAGGCCAGCCAAGUACCCCCUCCCAGUGGAUUCACUGUCCACGGCCUCCCAACAUCUCCAGACCGGCCAGGCUCCACCAGCCCCUUCGCUCCAUCAGCCACUGACCUGCCCAGCAUGCCUGAACCUGCCCUGACCUCCCGAGCAAACAUGACAGAGCACAAGACGUCCCCCACCCAAUGCCCGGCAGCUGGAGAGGUCUCCAACAAGCUUCCAAAAUGGCCUGAGCCGGUGGAGCAGUUCUACCGCUCACUGCAGGACACGUAUGGUGCCGAGCCCGCAGGCCCGGAUGGCAUCCUAGUGGAGGUGGAUCUGGUGCAGGCCAGGCUGGAGAGGAGCAGCAGCAAGAGCCUGGAGCGGGAACUGGCCACCCCGGACUGGGCAGAACGGCAGCUGGCCCAAGGAGGCCUGGCUGAGGUGCUGUUGGCUGCCAAGGAGCACCGGCGGCCGCGUGAGACACGAGUGAUUGCUGUGCUGGGCAAAGCUGGUCAGGGCAAGAGCUAUUGGGCUGGGGCAGUGAGCCGGGCCUGGGCUUGUGGCCGGCUUCCCCAGUACGACUUUGUCUUCUCUGUCCCCUGCCAUUGCUUGAACCGUCCGGGGGAUGCCUAUGGCCUGCAGGAUCUGCUCUUCUCCCUGGGCCCACAGCCACUCGUGGCGGCCGAUGAGGUUUUCAGCCACAUCUUGAAGAGACCUGACCGCGUUCUGCUCAUCCUAGACGGCUUCGAGGAGCUGGAAGCGCAAGAUGGCUUCCUGCACAGCACGUGCGGACCGGCACCGGCGGAGCCCUGCUCCCUCCGGGGGCUGCUGGCCGGCCUUUUCCAGAAGAAGCUGCUCCGAGGUUGCACCCUCCUCCUCACAGCCCGGCCCCGGGGCCGCCUGGUCCAGAGCCUGAGCAAGGCCGACGCCCUAUUUGAGCUGUCCGGCUUCUCCAUGGAGCAGGCCCAGGCAUACGUGAUGCGCUACUUUGAGAGCUCAGGGAUGACAGAGCACCAAGACAGAGCCCUGACGCUCCUCCGGGACCGGCCACUUCUUCUCAGUCACAGCCACAGCCCUACUUUGUGCCGGGCAGUGUGCCAGCUCUCAGAGGCCCUGCUGGAGCUUGGGGAGGACGCCAAGCUGCCCUCCACGCUCACGGGACUCUAUGUCGGCCUGCUGGGCCGUGCAGCCCUCGACAGCCCCCCCGGGGCCCUGGCAGAGCUGGCCAAGCUGGCCUGGGAGCUGGGCCGCAGACAUCAAAGUACCCUACAGGAGGACCAGUUCCCAUCCGCAGACGUGAGGACCUGGGCGAUGGCCAAAGGCUUAGUCCAACACCCACCGCGGGCCGCAGAGUCCGAGCUGGCCUUCCCCAGCUUCCUCCUGCAAUGCUUCCUGGGGGCCCUGUGGCUGGCUCUGAGUGGCGAAAUCAAGGACAAGGAGCUCCCGCAGUACCUAGCAUUGACCCCAAGGAAGAAGAGGCCCUAUGACAACUGGCUGGAGGGCGUGCCACGCUUUCUGGCUGGGCUGAUCUUCCAGCCUCCCGCCCGCUGCCUGGGAGCCCUACUCGGGCCAUCGGCGGCUGCCUCGGUGGACAGGAAGCAGAAGGUGCUUGCGAGGUACCUGAAGCGGCUGCAGCCGGGGACACUGCGGGCGCGGCAGCUGCUGGAGCUGCUGCACUGCGCCCACGAGGCCGAGGAGGCUGGAAUUUGGCAGCACGUGGUACAGGAGCUCCCCGGCCGCCUCUCUUUUCUGGGCACCCGCCUCACGCCUCCUGAUGCACAUGUACUGGGCAAGGCCUUGGAGGCGGCGGGCCAAGACUUCUCCCUGGACCUCCGCAGCACUGGCAUUUGCCCCUCUGGAUUGGGGAGCCUCGUGGGACUCAGCUGUGUCACCCGUUUCAGGGCUGCCUUGAGCGACACGGUGGCGCUGUGGGAGUCCCUGCAGCAGCAUGGGGAGACCAAGCUACUUCAGGCAGCAGAGGAGAAGUUCACCAUCGAGCCUUUCAAAGCCAAGUCCCUGAAGGAUGUGGAAGACCUGGGAAAGCUUGUGCAGACUCAGAGGACGAGAAGUUCCUCGGAAGACACAGCUGGGGAGCUCCCUGCUGUUCGGGACCUAAAGAAACUGGAGUUUGCGCUGGGCCCUGUCUCAGGCCCCCAGGCUUUCCCCAAACUGGUGCGGAUCCUCACGGCCUUUUCCUCCCUGCAGCAUCUGGACCUGGAUGCGCUGAGUGAGAACAAGAUCGGGGACGAGGGUGUCUCGCAGCUCUCAGCCACCUUCCCCCAGCUGAAGUCCUUGGAAACCCUCAAUCUGUCCCAGAACAACAUCACUGACCUGGGUGCCUACAAACUCGCCGAGGCCCUGCCUUCGCUCGCUGCAUCCCUGCUCAGGCUAAGCUUGUACAAUAACUGCAUCUGCGACGUGGGAGCCGAGAGCUUGGCUCGUGUGCUUCCGGACAUGGUGUCCCUCCGGGUGAUGGACGUCCAGUACAACAAGUUCACGGCUGCCGGGGCCCAGCAGCUCGCUGCCAGCCUUCGGAGGUGUCCUCAUGUGGAGACGCUGGCGAUGUGGACGCCCACCAUCCCAUUCAGUGUCCAGGAACACCUGCAACAACAGGAUUCACGGAUCAGCCUGAGAUGAUCCCAGCUGUGCUCUGGACAGGCAUGUUCUCUGAGGACACUAACCACGCUGGACCUUGAACUGGGUACUUGUGGACACAGCUCUUCUCCAGGCUGUAUCCCAUGAGCCUCAGCAUCCUGGCACCCGGCCCCUGCUGGUUCAGGGUUGGCCCCUGCCCGGCUGCGGAAUGAACCACAUCUUGCUCUGCUGACAGACACAGGCCCGGCUCCAGGCUCCUUUAGCGCCCAGUUGGGUGGAUGCCUGGUGGCAGCUGCGGUCCACCCAGGAGCCCCGAGGCCUUCUCUGAAGGACAUUGCGGACAGCCACGGCCAGGCCAGAGGGAGUGACAGAGGCAGCCCCAUUCUGCCUGCCCAGGCCCCUGCCACCCUGGGGAGAAAGUACUUCUUUUUUUUUAUUUUUAGACAGAGUCUCACUGUUGCCCAGGCUGGCGUGCAGUGGUGCGAUCUGGGUUCACUGCAACCUCCGCCUCUUGGGUUCAAGCGAUUCUUCUGCUUCAGCCUCCCGAGUAGCUGGGACUACAGGCACCCACCAUCAUGUCUGGCUAAUUUUUCAUUUUUAGUAGAGACAGGGUUUUGCCAUGUUGGCCAGGCUGGUCUCAAACUCUUGACCUCAGGUGAUCCACCCACCUCAGCCUCCCAAAGUGCUGGGAUUACAAGCGUGAGCCACUGCACCGGGCCACAGAGAAAGUACUUCUCCACCCUGCUCUCCGACCAGACACCUUGACAGGGCACACCGGGCACUCAGAAGACACUGAUGGGCAACCCCCAGCCUGCUAAUUCCCCAGAUUGCAACAGGCUGGGCUUCAGUGGCAGCUGCUUUUGUCUAUGGGACUCAAUGCACUGACAUUGUUGGCCAAAGCCAAAGCUAGGCCUGGCCAGAUGCACCAGCCCUUAGCAGGGAAACAGCUAAUGGGACACUAAUGGGGCGGUGAGAGGGGAACAGACUGGAAGCACAGCUUCAUUUCCUGUGUCUUUUUUCACUACAUUAUAAAUGUCUCUUUAAUGUCACAGGCAGGUCCAGGGUUUGAGUUCAUACCCUGUUACCAUUUUGGGGUACCCACUGCUCUGGUUAUCUAAUAUGUAACAAGCCACCCCAAAUCAUAGUGGCUUAAAACAACACUCACAUUUAUUCUGCUCACAUAUCUGUCAUUUGAGCAGGGCUCAGCGGGGACAGCUCCUUCUGUCCUACUCUGUGUCAGGUGGGGCAGCUUGAGGGUUGGGCUGGUGUCACCUGAAGACUCAUUCUUCUGUACGUCUGACAGGCAAUGCUGGCUGUUGGCUGGGGGCCUCAGUGCCACUACGGAAUAGUUGGCUAGGACCCCUCCAUGUGGGCUAGUUGGGCUUCCUCAUAGUAUGGUGGCUGGGUUGGAGGGUGUCCCAAAAAGAAAGGAGGGGAUAGAGAGAGACCACUUUUCAUAACCUAGCCUUAGAAGUCACACAGUAUUACUUCUGCUACAUAUAUAUGUUUUAAGAGGCAGGGUCUCACUCUGUCGCCCAGUCUGGAAUGCAGUGGUAUGAUCACGGCUCACUGCAGCCUCAACCUCCUGGGCUAAGUGAUCCUCCCACCUCAGCCUCCCGAAUAGCUGGGACUACAGGUGUGAGUCACCAAGCCCAGUUAAUCUUUAGUUUUAUUUUUGUAGAGCCAGGGUCUCACUAUGUUGCCCAGGCAGGUCUUGAACUCCUGGCCUCAAGUGAUUCUCCUGCCUCAGCCUCCCAAAGUGCUGGGAUUACAGGUGUGAACCACCACACCCAGCCCACUUCUGCCAUAUUCUGUUGGCCAGUGUGACAAGGAUUGCUACUGUCCUACCCACCCUCCUUUCACCACAUGUGCACAUGCACGUGUGUGCACGUACACACACAUACACACACACGCGUGCACACACCAGAGCCCACCUUGGCUCAAGUCCUCUUUUCUGAGAGGACUUUUCUUUGUGGCUUCCUAAAAUUCAGUGGAAAAUUAAUUGUUUGGGGAUGAGAAAGGUUGAAGCACCAAAAGCUUACCAAGGGGAAUGUUUGCCUCUGCCUCUGACACACAGCUCUGUCCUGGGAGUGAGCUGGUUUUUAGCGGAGACGGAGUCCCACCUUGGCUGCAGGGAGUCCGAAAGGGACUUGGAAGCUCCGCUUUCUACCCAGCGAGCUGCCGGCACGACUGUUGCUUUUCACUCGGGCAUAGUCUGCUCAGAAGCCCCAAUUCAAGACAUCUUAGCUUACUCCUGGUGGCAGUGGGAGCUGCCUGUUCAGCUCCAGCUCACCAGCCCCAGUGCCCACAGGAUCAGUCUGAUUCCCAAGCUCUGCUCCUCUCCCCAGCAAGUGAGAGCUGGGUGUCAAGAGGGUCUGAGGAAUCCAGACCCGGCUGCGUGGUUGAUGAUCUUUGCAGACAGGCAAGCACCUCCUGCCUCGAACUGGCUGCAAAGGGUAUCAGGUGCUGCCAUCCAGGUUCAGCUUGUAAAUAGCUCAGGUGUCACCCUGCAAGGGAUCCCUGCACUUGCAGACUCUACAGAGGCCAUGGGCCUCCUGUGUGUGCGCCUACAGGAGUGAGCACUAAGGUGUGCUCUGAUCAUCCACUGUGCCAUGUGCCAGGUUUUUGGUCUGACCCACUGCUUUUGGUCUGUGUGAUGAUGAAAUGAGGUCAGAGCCUGCAGUUAUUAACACUAACGAUUUGUUAAUGAUAGCUACUGUUUAUUAUUUUAUUUAAUUUUUUUGAGACAGAGUUUUCACUCUUAUUGCCCACGCUGGAGUGCAGUGGCAUGAUCUCGGCUCACUGCAACCUCUGCCUCCUGGGUUCAAGCAAUUCUCCCACCUCAGCCUCCCAAGUAGCUGGGAUUACAGGCAUGCACCACCACGCCUGGCUAAUUUUUGUAUUUUUAGUAGAGAUGGAGUUUCACCAUGUUGGCCAGGCUGGUAAUCUGCCUGCCUUGGCCUCCCAAAGUGCUGGGAUUACAGGGGUGAGCCACCGCACCCGGCCACUACUGUUUAUUUAAUGAGCAGAUACAUGCAAAGCCCUUAUCACAGUGCAAGGGAAAUUCAAAGCGCUCAGAAAGUAUUAGCUCAAUAAGUGAUGACUGUGUGCCAGACACUGUGCUAAACUCCUACUCAAGAGGGAUAAGAGUCUAGGGGCAAGUGGCAGAGACUCUAGAACGAGAUUGCCUGGGCUCAACGCCCACCUCACCACUUACUUAUGCAAGCUAGUUCUCUGUGCCUCAGUCUCCUCAUUUGUAAAAUGGGCAUAACCACAGCACCUUCUUUAUAGGAUUAUGUGAAGGUGUGGUGAGCUAAUACGUUAAGAAUUGGAGCUCAAUAACAUGUUGGCUGUCAUUAUUACAUAUAUCUGUGUUUCAUUCUUGCCUCUGGCUGGAAUGUUCUUCCCAGCUCUCCAUAUGGCUGAUUUCUCAUCCUUCGGGACUUGCCCCAUUCUCCAACCCCAUCACUAGUUUUAUCUUUUUCACUUAUUUAUGCAGUCUGCUCUUGUCCUAGGACAUGAGCUCCAGGAGGGCGGGAAACAUCUCGCUUUGUACACUGCUGUGCCCUCUGUACCCAGCAAGGCGCCUGUGUAUAAUAGGUGCUCAAUAACAUAAAAUGAACAAAUAAUCCUCACCUAACGGUUUCAUUCAUUCUGCAAAUACAUACUGACAGCACAGUCAUGAAUAAGAUGUUCCUGCCCUGGUGAGUCUUAUAUUUUAGCAAAUUAAAAAAACUCUUUGGACAGGGCUGCCAGGUGAGGUUGGCCAGUCUGUACACUGCACAAAGGCACCUGGGACAAGGGGGAACAUGGGGGCUGCAAACCAGUCUGGGUUCUGCUUGCCAAACUGGGAGUCCUGGUGUGGAGCCUUUUAACCCAGAGGGGCAUCUUUUCGUAGUUAACGCACAGUCAUCGUAAGAUGUGGAUAAAUUACUGUCUCCGUGUCACAGAUCUAAGUGAUACUUAUAGUCACACUCCUAUAAAGGAAUGGACUUCUGACUUCUUUGGAGGACCUCUCUGCAGGGACAGGCACAGUGUGCCGGAAGUGCCCCUGAACCCCAUUUGUCAGGUGGUAAAGCGCUGCUCGGAGGAAUCAGGGCAUGAUAGUGCAAUUCCAUGUCCAGUGGAUUGUAAGUCCACGCACCUUCCAAAUGGUCACUCUUCCUCGCAGGCCUCUCUCUGCAUACAAAUGUCUCCCUCCUGACGCUCACCUUUUUCCCUGGGGCUCUCAAAUGUCUUCUUUUCAGAUUUCGUAGCUUUUCUUUCUUUAGCAUCACUUGAGGGCAAGUGGUGCUCCAACUGUCUCCCCCCAGAGUUCUGCCGCCUGUACUCUCCCACACCUCAGUCUCCUCGCCUGUAGAAAGGGGUCAAUCGUUUGAACCCUGCUUCACUUGGUGUGUAUGUGAAGGUGCUUUGAAAUCAAGUGCUCUGCAAACUGGAGAGAAUUACUGCUUGUAUUCCGUGAAACUACAAGCUCCCAAUUCCACUCAUUUAAUCCCUCUCUUGCUCUGUUGCCCAGGCUGGAAUGCAGUGGCAUGAUCUCAACUCACUGCAACCUCUGCCUCCCUGGUUUCAAGCAAUUCUCCUGCCUCAGCCUCCCGAGUAGCUGGGACUAUAAGUGUGCGCCACUAUGCCUGGCUAAUUUUUUUGUAUUUUUAGUAGAGAUGGGGUUUCACCGUGGUGGCCAGGCUGGUCUCGAACUCCUAACCUCAAGUGAUCUGCCCGCCUCGGCCUUCCAAAGUGCUGGGAUUACAGGCAUGAGCCACCAUGCCAAGCCCUUCCCCCCUAUCUUUAAUGAAGGUCUACCAUGUGCCUGACACAGGGGAUACCCACCCCCACUUCUAUGGGAUUCAGGCCUGGUUUCCAGCUUGGCCUUCAGGCUUUUCCCACCACACCCCAAAUGCUGUCCCUGGCUUGUGGAGUGGGGCAGGGGGCCAGCCUGGGACUUUCACGCCAGCCCGACUGGGGCAGACUCUCUCAACCCCACUGGAUCUUCUGCUGUUUGUCAGCCACAAGGUUCUGCCUAGAACUCCUUUCCCGAAUCUCAAAGUUAAAAAAAAAGGCAGGGCCCCAGGGGUUGGAGUUGCAUACAUUUUUUUUUAAUCCAAAGAAGUAAGCCUCCUAAGUAUUGCUUAGACAGGUUUAUCAGAAUUAAGUAGGCACAACACUCAUACUUUCAGAAAAGCAUUUCCAGCCAGGGGAGUAACGUGGCACUCACCAGCAUGAUGUCUGUUUUGCCAACUUGCUGAAGAACGAGUAACCUGAAAUGAAGGAGCGAGAAUCCCACCCUCAGCCCCCCAACAGCUUCCUCAGCUUCUUUUUCUUCUGAGUCACCCCUGAAACAGUCGCUGCAUCUAAGACCAGCCUCGGGCUAAACCCAGCUGGCCUGAAGGCUCAACUCACAUCAAACGGAGCUGGGAGUCGCUUUUGCGUGUGUCCGCAGUUUGAAGUGUCCUCUCCGAAGGUGAAGUGGGGGAAGCAGGUGCGCUCCGGGAUGAAGUGCAGGGAGGCAAACUCUGGCUGGGUUCCUGUAAACAUCCAUCGCAGCUGCAAAUAAUCAGAAGCCAAGGCCAGGCCAUCGAUUUGACACUGCAGGCAGAUGAGGUCUUGGGAUGCCUCUUGCGUUCCCCCUUCUGUGGGAGCAGGUGCCUUCCCAACCUCAGCACUCAGUCCCAAUCUCUCUUCCACUCUCCUGGGUUCAAACAGGAACCUCUCUGUUGGCACGAAGCUUUUGAGGGGAGCAGGUCUAACAAGAAGGAAAAAGGGGGGUUAUUAGCACGGAAGCCCCACCCUGCCACCAGGUUGGCUGGGGACAGGGACCAAUCCACCAGGCUCGGGAGGCUUGGGGUGGGGCAGGGAAGUCUUCCUCCAUCCCUCAAAUUUAGGGAACCACUGGGAGCCCCAGACUCAGGCUGAAAAUGUCUUUCUGCAAAUAUAAAACUCUUUUUAAUGAAUUUGCCUAAUUUCUCAGAGACCCUGGGCUGGAGAACCAGUGCAAUGUCACACGGGAGAGGAAGGACUGUCCUGUUUAUUGGGAGGGAGGAGGGGGAUGCUGGUGCAGCCUGCUCAGGAGUCACCCAGGGUCUGAGGGCUGACUUGCAGCUCUGGGCCAGCUGAGCCAGCGCUGGGUAGUGGGCAGGGCUUGGCAACACCUUCCACCUUGCCCGGAAAAAUGCUUUGCAACCUACAGGAAGGCAAUAGCCACAGCCAAGUUACUCAGCAGCCCCACUUGGCUCUUUCUCCCAGGAUGCAGCAUCAUCUCCAUGGCCUGGCCCCCUGGCACGUCCCCGUUUCCCACUGCCUUCUCUGUGUGCCUAGCCGGGUGCCAGUGUCUCUGUAGCACCUCGUGUUCCCAUGCCCAACCCCUCUGCAGCCCCCUCAAGCCCUGCUCUGAUUCCAAGCCUCAUCUCCCAGCUCACUAUCCUUUCCGCAAACUUCACUGAACAUCUCGCAGAACUUGUAUGUUAAACAUGUGACAUGUAUUGUUGUUUGACAGGGUGCUAUUGACAUUUGGGGUAGGACAAUUCUUGGAGGUGGGGUGGCUGUUCUGGGCACUGAGCAUUUAGCAGCAUCUCUGGCUCCAGGCCACUAAAUGCCAGUAGCACCCCUGGCCACUGGAACAACUAAAAAUGCCCUCCUACCCUAUUUCCAAGGUCGACCUAAGGGGGCGGAACUGUUUCCAUUGAGACCCAUGCAUCGUAUAGGAUAAGAAACUGAGGUUCUUAUCAUUUAAUAGGAUAAGAAAUUGAGGUUCAGAGAAGCCAAGUAACCUGCCUAAAGAUGCACAGCUAUGAGAGGCAAAGCUGGCACUGGCUUGGUAAUAACGAUGGAAACGGUCUGAAUGAGAGCAGGUACCAUUUCCUGAGCUCUUAGCAGACGCUGAGGACCCUGCUAAGUGCCAUGAGACCUUAGCAGAGGCUGUGGGUGCCCCGCCCCAUUCCCUCCACUCACUCUUCCUUGCAGGUCGACCUGCCCUUCUUUGCUGAGGCCUUUCUCUGCCUCCAGAGCCUGCUUGGUCCUCAGGCUGUAAGUGCAGGCAGAGCUAAUGUCUCUCCAUAGCUGCCCUCCACCAGCCUGCUCCUGAGACACCUGCUGGCCAGCAGCCUGAAGCAGAAUCCUUUACUCAGAUUCAGCCGCACAGAUGCUCACUGCAGAGAUCUCCAAGGCCUGUGGUCAUCCUUGAGCCCAUCUCAGAUUUGUGUGGAUAGGGUGUUAGAGAACAUGGAAUCAGCUGGAUAGAGUGGUUCAUGCUUGUAAUCCCAGCACUUUGGGAGGCUGGGGUGGGAGGAUCACUUGAGGCCAGGAGUUUGAGACCAGCCUGGGCAACACAGUGAGACUGUCUCUAUAAAAAAUUUAAAAAUUAGCCAGGCAUAGUGUAGUCUCAGCUACUUGGAAGGCUGAGGCAGGAGGAUUGCGUGAGCCCAGCAGUUCAAGGCUGCAGUGAACUAUGACUGUGCCCCUGCACCCAGCCUGGGUGACAGAGACCCUGUCUCAAAAAAAAGAGAAGAUGGAAUCACUCGGUGAGGACCUCACUCCUCUCCCAGUCCUGUGACCACAAACCGCAUCCCCGACAGUCCCAGCCAGGCGCUAGUCUGGCUGUAGCUGCCCUCUUGUGUGCAGAUCUCCAGUCUGAAUGGGCUACACGUGGAAUUUACUAACACUCCGGUUUUCAUUGUGUUUAUCUGUAGGGUUACCUUCUAUUUAUAGCAAGUGAUGCCAAGUUUCCAUUUCUGGUAGUAAUAUAGUUUUUCUUUUCCAAGUCGCUCACACCUGUAAUCCCAACACUUUGGGAGGCUAAGGUGGGUGGAUCAGUUGAGAUCAGGAGUUUGAGACCAGCCUGGCCAACAUGGCGAAAUGAGGUCAAGACUAGCCUGGCCAACAUGGCGAAACCGCGUCUCUACUAAAAACAAACAAACAAAAAUACAAAAUUCGCUGGGCAUGGUGGCAGGUGCCUGAGGUCCCAGCUACUCGGGAGGCUGAGGCAGAAGAAUCGCUUGAGCUAGGGAGGCAGAGGUUGCAGUGAGCCGAGAUCACGCCACUGCACUAUAGCCUAGGUGACAGAGUGAGACUCUGUCUCAAAAAAACACAAAAGUUUCUCUUUUCAAAACAUUUUACUUUAAAAGGAGCCAAUUUAAAGAAAACUGUUAAUAGUUCAGGUAACAGGCAGAUACAGGAAAAGCUGCUGACAGUGUUGUAUGAGGUUUGAGGAUUUUGAUCCAAGCUGGUCCCACUCAGUCCAUAGCAGAGAAUGAAAGGGCCCAGAGAGGGUGGUGACCUCUGCCUGAAGUCACACAGUGAGUCGAGGACAGGGAGGUGACCCCAGGUUUCUAUGUGUAGGGCGGGAGGAUGUUCUGGGACACAGUUCAAUUCUCAUUUGUCACACACUUUGGCUAUUAGAGAUCAACCCCUUCGCUCCUGUGUCUUGCAAUGGCAGCCUUGGCAAACGCUAAAUGAAAAUCGUGACAACACUUGUGUUAUGAAGCAUUUACUUUGUGUUCACCUUGUACUACUCGAACUCAUGUCUUAACUCACUUAUCCCUCAAAAACAACUCUAGGAGGUAGGGCCAAGUAGGACCAUCAUCCCUGCAUUUCACAUGGAGCUCAGAGAGGUUAAGCAAGCCGUGCAAGGCCACACAGCUCAUAAAUGGCAGAGCCAGGAUUUGAACCCCCGUGGCCUGACCCCAAAGCCGAAACCACUCGGCACUGCAGGUUCGUCCCUUUUCUCUGAGAUGGGGGUAUCCAAUCUUUUGGCUUCCCUGGGCCACAGUGGAAGAACUGUCUGGGGCCACAUAUAAAAUAUACUAAUGAUAGCUCAUGAGCUAAAAAAUAAAACAAAAUCACACACACACACACAAAAAAACACAAACCAAAAAAAAAAUUCUUUUUUUUUUUUUUUUUUUGAGACAGGGUCUUGCUUUGUCACCCAGGCUGGAGGGCAGUGGCAUGAUCUUGGCUCACUGCAGUUCCAGGUUCAAGCAAUUCUCAUGCCUCAGCCUCCUGAGUAGCUGGGACUACAGGCGCAUGUCACCAUGCCUGGCUAAUUGAUGUAUUUUUUAGUAGAGAUGGGGUUUCACCAUGUUGGCCAGGCUAAAAUCUCAUAACGUUUUAAGAAAGUUUAUGAAUCUGUGUUGGGCCACAGUCAAAGCCGUCCUGAGCUGUAUGCAGCCUACAGGCCGCACCACGGAUUGAACAAGUUUCUUCUAAGGCAUCAAGAGCCCCAGGCUGAAAAGCACCCCAGAGCUGGAGCUUAUAGAACCCAGGGCAGCAGGUUCUCCAACCUUCUGACAUCAUCAGAGCACAGCAGACAAGUUAUCAGCCACUAGAUUUUUUUCCCCCUUUCUGAAACUGUAACCUUUCAUUCCAGCCAUUCCCCAGAGCUGGACAGAGGACGUGGCUGGCUGGCUGGUUUCUGUAGUCAGAAUGACAGUUGGGUGCUAGAUCCCCUUCGUGAAGCAAUGUCUUAGCUCAGUAACUCUGCAGAGAAGCUGCCUGGUUCAGGAUGUGGCUUAAGUAAGAAGAUGGCCCUGGCGUUUUACGCGCACUGGUGGGUGAGGCUCUGAAAGUGGUAGAAGGGAAUUCUUUCCUAGAGUUCAGCUGCCCGCUGUCCUGCUCCUCAGGGCAAAUGCUGUGAGAUCUGCAUUUAGCCUGUCUGUGCUGAUUGUGGUUCUGCCCCUUCCUGGCUGUGUGACCUCAGACAAGUCACCCACCCUCUCUGGGCCAGUUUCCUCAUCUGGAAAAGGGGACAGUGCCCACCACAUUGGGCUGUUUGUGUCCAUGGAGUGCCUGACAAUACCCAGCACACACGAGACAUCAGUACAGGGUGGUUCCUUCCCUCCUUAGCCCCACCUGUUCCCAGGUAGAAACCAAUACCGGCAGGGAACCUUCUCAAGGCUAGGGGCCUUCUGAAAGCAGCAGCACUUUUCCUCCUUCAAAGACCUUGCCUUCUAGAAACCCAUUGCUCAUUCCUUUCUCCAUGUACCAAAAAAUCAAUUAAAGUGGCUAAAGACAGACGUCACCCUCCCCUACUCACGCAGCCAUUCUGAUCCUCCACGCUGGUGACAGGCUAUGUGGCAGGAGGGUCUCUACCUUAUCUCAGAAUGAAGGCAUGGCUGGGGUCUGGCUGUCUCCUGGUGGCCGGAAGGAGACAGACGGCAAAGGAGAAGCUGCCUGUCUCUGCACAGGUCCAUGUCCCUGAGGAAAGCCAACGUCACAGAGAAAUGAUGACCACUUUCUCAAACCUGGCUUCGGAUUUGCACGUUGGCUGCCAAAGCUGAUCAGCAGCGGGCUUUGUGAAGAUGCCUGGUCUACCACGUGCCUCCAGCUGGUCACGCCCAAGACUCCCUGAGCCCUCUGGAAGGGCAGCACUUGCCCAGUGCCUCCCUCCAGGUCCUGCCACAUCCAAGAACCACCUGGACUAUUAUUUACUUAGUAUUUUAAACCAAUGUACUUUUUAAACUCCAAUUUUUUAAUAAGAUCAUUUAUGUCACCAUAUAACACCCAAAGCAGUAGAAUUUGUCAUACACAGAAGGCAAUGCUAAAAAUACAAUGAAAAUGGAACCAGGAAGUCUAGCUUGAUACCCUUGGCCUGUAUAACUGAGCCUUGUGCCAGUUAAAAGGGCAAAGCAGUAGGUGCUCAGGGGGUGUCGGGGCCCUGAGAGCUGAUCUGAUCCGCUGCUGCGUAUUCACUACCGCCCUGGGACGCCUCCAGCAGACCACCUCACUGGGGGAAACAUCAGGACAGCGUGGCCAGGAGCCCAAUGCUGCCACCUCAUAGAUGGGUAUCUGAGAUGAGUCAUCGAACUUCUGCAAGCCUCAGUUUCCUCCCUGGUCUAAUGGAACCCUCCUUGGCGGCUUCACAGGGUGAUGCUUGGGGCAGGUGAUGGAGAUGUGGGAGAGGCAGUUAUUUUUAACCACCCAGCCAAGCCCCUUGCCAGGAGGGACUCCCAGAAAUGAAGCCUUACCCUUGAGGGAGUUCCCCGCCACUCCAAGCUUGGGGCCUGGGAUGGCAGCUGUGAGGGCACCAGCACCAUCUGGGGACUCGCUGGGUACCAAUUAUCACCGCCCUUGGGCUACUUCAAAGGCUGCCCACACAGACACACCCUCCUUGGUAACCAGUCCUCAGGAGGAAGGGCACCCAAGGAAAGGGGGAAGGCUUCCUGGGCUAGAGCCCCUUCAGGGUCUGACACGCCAUUGACACUGACCACGUCAUUCAUUAAGCAAGCACCAACUAUACAUCAUUCACUAUCCCAAUCUAAUUUGCACAAGCCCUUAGGCAGGUGCUACUAUUAUCCCUGUUUUACAGAGAAGGAAACCGAGGCUUAGGAGAUGAAGUCUGAGGUGUUGGUGGAGCUGGGAUUUAAACCAAAAUAUGUCCAACUGCAAAGCAUGUAAGUAACAAUUUUAGAGGGUAUACGGAGGUGACCCUAAGUAACAAGGAAUCACAUAUAGUGAGCAAGCAAUUUGCUUUUCAGUUUUUGGUCAAUCCUUAUGAUUAUUUAGAGGAGAAAGUUCAGUUUGGUGCUGGUAUAUCUUAUGUUUAUCACCCGACAGUUGUUAAUCUCUUUUUAACAAAGAAUACAGGCCAAGGCCCUGUGACUUUAGCUGGCUUUGGUAUUUGGCCAAAAGUUAAUGACUUUGGCAGUUAGUGUUUUUAUCCAUGCCAAGCGAUGAUGAUUUUCUCUUUAGUGACAGACAUUUUUUAAAAAAUAAAUUCACAUAAAAAAGUAGUUUUACAGAUGAAGCACUAAAACUAGUGCAUUUCAUCUUAAACUGCAAAUUAUAAAGGGAAUAAUAGUAACUUGACAGUGGAGAGACCUGGCAGACACCACCUUCACCAACUGAUCAAAGUUAACAUCGCCAGAAAGGGGACAGAUGGCAUGUGCCUCUCGAUAAGAUGCACUGAAGACACACACUCACUUCUGCAAUAUUCCUGCCAAGAAUGCCUCAUCUGAAUCUAAUCUCGAGUAUAACCAUCAGACAAACCCAAAUUGAGAGACAGUUUACAAAACACCAGCCUUGUACUCUGCUUAAUAUGUCAAUGUCACAAGAGAGAAAGACAGACUGAAGAGCUGAUCCAGACUGAAGAAGGCUCGAGAUUAAUGCAAAAGCUGAUCUGGGAUUGCAUCUUGGACCUCAACUCUCCCCUUUUUAUUGUUAAGGGACACUACUGGGACAAUUUUUUUUUUUUUUCGUUUUGAGACAGGGUCUCGCUCAGUCACCCAGGCUGGAGUGCAGUGGUGGAAUAAUAACUCACUGCAGCCUUGAACUCCCGGACUCAAGCAAUCCUCCUGCCUGAGCCUUCCGAGUAACUGGGACUAUGGGCGUGUACCACAACACCUCGCUAUUUUUUUUUUCCUACUUUUUGUAGAGACGGGGUCUCACUAUGUUGCCCAGGCUGGUUUCAAACUCAAGUGAUCCUUCCACCUCAGCCUCUAUAAAAUUUGAAUAAAGUUGUAGAUGAGAUUGGUCAUAGGAUUGUAUAGUGUAUCAAUAUUAGAUUUGCUGAUUUUGACAACCCUACUGUGGUUAUGCAAAUUUGUCCUUGUUCUAAGGAAAUAAAUACUGAAUUAUUUAGGAGUAAA